CUCAUUCGUUCCCAGCAGGCCCUGCGCGCGGCAACAUGGCGGGGUCCAGGUGGAGGUCUUGAGGCUAUCAGAUCGGUAUGGCAUUGGCGUCCGGGCCCGCAAGGCGGGCGCUAGCUGGCUCCGGGCAGCUCGGCCUUGGGGGCUUCGGGGCCCCGAGACGCGGGGCGUAUGAGUGGGGCGUGCGCUCCACGCGGAAGUCGGAGCCUCCUCCCCUGGAUAGGGUGUACGAGAUCCCUGGACUGGAGCCCAUCACCUUUGCGGGGAAGAUGCACUUCGUGCCCUGGCUGGCGCGGCCGAUCUUUCCGCCCUGGGACCGCGGCUACAAGGACCCAAGGUUCUACCGCUCGCCCCCUCUUCACGAGCAUCCGCUGUACAAAGACCAGGCCUGCUAUAUCUUUCACCACCGUUGCCGCCUUCUCGAGGGUGUAAAGCAGGCCCUCUGGCUCACCAAGACCAAGUUAAUAGAAGGCCUUCCCGAGAAAGUGCUUAGCCUUGUUGAUGAUCCAAGGAACCACAUAGAGAACCAAGACGAGUGCGUUCUGAAUGUGAUCUCUCACGCCCGUCUCUGGCAGACCACUGAGGAAAUCCCCAAGAGAGAGACCUACUGCCCGGUCAUCGUGGACAACCUAAUACAGCUGUGUAAAUCUCAGAUUCUCAAGCAUCCUUCUCUGGCCAGGAGGAUCUGUGUCCAAAACUCCACGUUUUCUGCUACCUGGAACCGAGAGUCUCUUCUCCUUCAAGUCCGUGGUUCUGGUGGAGCCCGACUGAGCACUAAGGAUCCUCUGCCCACCAUCGCCUCCAGAGAGGAGAUUGAAGCUACUAAGAAUCAUGUUCUAGAGACCUUCUACCCCAUAUCACCCAUCAUCGAUCUUCAUGAAUGCAAUAUUUAUGAUGUGAAAAAUGACACAGGAUUCCAGGAAGGCUAUCCUUACCCCUAUCCCCAUACCCUGUACUUACUGGACAAAGCCAAUUUACGACCACACCGCCUUCAACCAGAUCAGCUGCGGGCCAAGAUGAUCCUGUUUGCUUUUGGCAGUGCCCUGGCUCAGGCCCGGCUCCUCUAUGGGAAUGAUGCCAAGGUCUUGGAGCAGCCCGUGGUGGUGCAGAGCGUGGGCACGGAUGGACGUGUCUUCCAUUUCCUAGUGUUUCAACUGAAUACCACAGACCUGGACUGUAACGAGGGUGUCAAGAAUUUGGCCUGGGUGGACUCAGACCAGCUCCUCUAUCAGCAUUUUUGGUGUCUCCCAGUGAUCAAAAAGAGAGUGGUUGUGAAAAAUAAAAGACAUUCCAGCGGACCAAAAUGUGUUUGCAAGACAAGAAAUGGAAAAUGGCUUUUAGACGGCCCCCAAAUAUUUAAAGUGAGAUGGAUACCUUCCCUCCCAACCCACCUUCCGCCAAGGCCAUCGCGACUCCACAAGAACACAGAAUUUGCAGGCCCAGGAAAAGAAGGCAGACGCCUCAAACACAAAACAUCUUGUUAUGCACCAGGAACAAAAACUGUGCCCAAGAAGUCACCUUGCAUUUUGUAAUCAGUGUAAUAAACUCCAACCCACAUUCCCCAAACAUGUCAGGAAGGGCUGCGGAAAAAAGAUGUCCCUUUAAUAAAACGUUAUCAACAUAUAUCGUACACAAACUA